GACACAUUUCUGGUGUUUUAAGAUGCCUGAGCCAGCCAAGUCUGCUCCCGCCCCGAAGAAGGGCUCCAAGAAGGCAGUGACCAAAGCGCAGAAGAAAGAUGGCAAGAAGCGCAAGCGCAGCCGCAAGGAGAGUUACUCUGUGUACGUGUACAAGGUGCUGAAACAGGUCCAUCCCGACACUGGCAUCUCUUCCAAGGCCAUGGGCAUCAUGAAUUCUUUCGUUAACGACAUAUUUGAGCGCAUCGCGGGCGAGGCUUCCCGCCUGGCGCAUUACAACAAGCGCUCGACCAUCACCUCCAGGGAGAUCCAGACGGCCGUGCGCCUGCUGCUUCCCGGAGAGCUGGCCAAGCACGCCGUGUCGGAGGGCACCAAGGCCGUCACCAAGUACACCAGCUCCAAGUAAACAUUCCAAGGGGAGACAACAGCUUUUAGACAUAUCUUUUCCAACAGUCGUCACUGCUGGACACUGUUUCAUCUUGCAAAUAAACCAAUGAAAAUGAGUGAUCCUAGAAGAAGAUAAAUGGAGGUAUUUUGAACAAUCAAAGAAGGACAAAUGAACACCUGGCUGAGAAAAAUUAGCUCUUUUUUCUAUGCAUAAAACUAUUAAAAUAUUCUUCAUAGAAAUUUAUGACACAGGAAACAUAAAGACAAAAUUAAAAUAACUCCUAGUAUCUCCUAUUCUUUUUAUAUGUAUAUUAUAUAUACUCAUAUUCAUAUAUACAUAUAUCUCACAUCAUGUAUCAUAUAUAAAAUAAAUUUAGGUGUCAUGAUAUAUAUUUAGAUAAAUAUACUUAGAAACUUUUUUAUGGAUGUAUAAUUUAUGGAUAUAUUGAUAAUUAUGUAUUUGUUAUUGACUACUUCAAUUGAUUCCCAUUUUUAUGCAUUAUAUUAUAGAUUAUAUAGCUCACACAUCUUUGUACAUAAAUCUUUGUUCAAAUAUUAUUUCCUAAGGAUAGACUUCAUGAAGUGGAAAUACUAAAUCAAAAGUGAAAAACAUUUUCUAAGGUUCUUAACAUAUACAUUGCCAAAUUGCUAUUCAGGAUCAUACCAAUUUAUAAUCCCAAAAUAAUAUGGAAAUUCCUGUUUUAUAGCACUCAUAUUUACAAUAAAUUUUAAAAAUCACUGUUAACCUAAUAGUCCUUCAAAAGAAAAAAAAAUUGAAAUUACAUUAUUUUAAUGACUCUAUUAGUGAGGGUCAUUCUUCCCAUGUUUCUUGUUAGCCAUGACCCUAUAAGAAAUAAACUGCACUGCAAAAUGAUAAACAUGACAUCAAUCAUUACAUGGGAAGGCACUAUAUAAAGAAUAAUACCUUAGGUUAAGGCCACAUAAAUAUUUAUCAGGUGCCUUUUCUGCGGAGGACUCUGAAGGGAUACUAAACUGCAUUUAGCUGCAUGCAACUGAAACUACUUUUACCUACAUUGUCUCUUAUAAACAUUAUAACUACUCUUUGAGAAAGUGUUUACUAUGGACUGAAUUGUCUCCCCAUCCCCCCAAAUUCAUAUAUUGAAGCCAUAAACCCCAAUAUGACUCUAUUCCUAGACAGGACUUAUAAGAGGUAAUUAAGGUUAAAUGAGGUCAUUAGGAUGGGUUCCUAACUGGAUAGGAUUGGUGGCCUUAUAAGAAGAGGAAGAUUCUGCACUUGGUCUUCCAAAUUAAAUAAUUUAUUUAAAAGAAAAAAAAAAAAGAGGAAGAGAGGGAGCUCUGCACAUAUACUGAGGAAAGGCUAUGUGAGCUCUCACAGUGAGAAGGUAGCACUCUACAAGCCAGCAAGAGAGCCCUCAACAGAAUCCAGCCAUGCUAUACCCUGCUCUGAGACUUCCAGCCUCCAGAACUGUGAUAAAAUUUUGUUGUUUAAACCACACAAUCUAUGGUAUUUUUUUAUGGCAGCCCAAGCCAACAAAGACAGCAUCAUUGCUGUCACUUACAGACAAGAAAACUAAGACUAGGAGAGAGAAAAGUUAAACUUGUCCAAGGUCACAAAAGCCAGAAACAAGUGAGGUGAGAAGUUGACCUUGUUCUCCUCAAUCCAAGGCCAGGACUCCUCCACUCCACAUGUAGAUAGCCACCUCACAGUCAACAGCCAAAUGUCCACACCCCAGAGUCAGCAUUAGACCAAGAUGUCUUACCAGGAGACAAAUGCCUCAUCUUGAAUAAAUAUGAUCUAACAACUUACCCAUGUAAAACAUUGAAUCUCAUGAGAAACAAAAAUGCAAAGUAUGUAGAAAACUAUGUUUACCACUUAACUGACAGUGAUAAAAAGCUUAAUGAUAUCCUUAUAGUCUUGGAGGGGUUUGUAUAUGUGGUGAAACAGGUGCUCACGCACUGCUGAUAGACUGUAAAUUGGUCCUAGAGAGAAAAAUAAAUAAACUGGAAGGAGA